GAGGUACCCGCUUGCUUUAUGGGAAAAGGCUGCUCCGGAACUGCCCUACUUUAGACUUUUUCAUGGUUAUCAAUCUGUACAAAGAAUCACCAAACUGAUAAAGCAGGAACCAGAGGGCAAAUCACGCUGCCAAGACAACUGUGUAAUUCGCUCGAAAAAGAAACGGUGAGCCUCUCCAGCAGACUGGGUAAACUGGCAAGGGAUUUUACGACAUAGUUGGAGAUUGGAGAGUUACAGAAACUUUUCCGGUUUUUUACAAGUUUUAAAGGAGUGAUUGAGUGUCAAAGGAAAAGCAGAGAAAAUACAGGCACAAUUUAAAGACAGCAGGAAGAAGAGUGUUCAGAGAGCAUUUUUCUCUUUAGGGUGAAGUUUGAAAGCAUCAUGCCCAGAUUAUCAGUGGAUUUUUGAAAGAUGGAGUCUCGCUCUGUCACCCAGGCUGGAGUAUAGUGGUGUGAUCUUGGCUCACUGCAACCUCUGCCUCCCAGGUUCAAGCGAUUCUCCUGCCUCAGCCUCUCGAGUAGCUGGAAUUACAGGUCUGGCAGAAGGAACAGUAUCAACUGACUGAGUAGGUCUCAUUGGCAGUUGUGAUUCAGAGACCUAGAAAGCUGAACCCACGGCUGGCAAGAAGAGGAUGGUUUGUGGGACCUGGGCUGAUGUCUGAUGAAAUUUUAAGCCCCAGCUAUAGCUACUACAAAGAAAAGUGGCUGAUGAUAAGCAUGUAACUCAAAAGACAGAGUUUUGCCAUGUUGCCCAGGCUGGUCCCAAACUCCUGAGCUGAGGUGACCCUCCCGCCUCCACCUCCCAGAGUGCUGGGAUUACAGAAGACAAUGUAUAUAAAAAUAUGCAAGAAUCACAGGAAACCCACAUAUCCAACCACCUAGAUGAAGUUGUUGCUGCUGUUAGCAUCACUCAUAGAAAGAAGUUCCAAAACAAGCUGCUUCAGACAGCACUAUUCCAGCCUCCUCGAGAGAAACUCCACCUCUGUGAAGAGAAAGCAAAGUCCUAUUCCAACAGUCAUGAGUACAAACAGGCCGUCCAUGAGCUUGUGCGUUGCGUAGCACUGACAAGAAUUUGCUAUGGAGACUCACAUUGGAAACUAGCAGAGGCACAUGUUAAUCUGGCUCAAGGCUACCUCCAGCUGAAAGGACUGUCACUGCAAGCAAAACAACAUGCAGAAAAAGCCAGACAAAUCCUCGCCAACUCCAUUGUGCCUCCCUAUAGUGAGAAUACAGAUGUUUUCAAGUUUUCCAUUGAGCUUUUCCAUACCAUGGGCAGAGCUUUACUCUCCCUUCAAAAAUUUAAGGAAGCUGCAGAGAAUUUGACAAAAGCAGAGAGACUUUCAAAGGAGCUGCUACAAUGUGGAAGAAUUAUAAAGGAAGAAUGGAUAGAAAUUGAAGCACGGAUCAGAUUAUCAUUUGCACAGGUGUAUCAAGGUCAGAAGAAGUCAAAAGAAGCUUUGUCCCACUAUCAAGCAGCUUUGGAAUAUGUUGAGAUCAGUAAAGGUGAAACAAGUCGUGAGUGUGUACCCAUAUUGAGAGAAUUAGCAGGUGUAGAGCAAGCCCUGGGACUCCACGAUGUAUCCAUCAACCACUUCCUCCAGGCACAUCUUAUCAUCCUGAGUAGAAGCCCCUCUCAAGUGGAGGCAGCAGACUCGGCACACAUCGUCGCCCAUGCUGCUGUCGCUUCAGGGAGACACGAGCACCAUGAUGUAGCUGAGCAGUAUUUUCAAGAGAGCAUGGCUCAUCUUAAGGAUUCUGAAGGGAUGGGAAGAACCAAAUUUCUUUCAAUUCAAGAUGAAUUUUGCCAUUUUCUACAAAUGACUGGACAAAAAGAGAGAGCAACCUCGAUCCUGAGAGAGUCCCUGGAAGCCAAAGUGGAAGCAUUUGGCGAUUUCAGUCCCGAGGUGGCAGAGACAUACCGGCUCCUGGGAGGAGCAGACCUGGCGCAGGGGAACCACAGUGGGGCCCGCAAGAAACUGAAGAAGUGUCUCCAGAUCCAGACCCUCUUAUAUGGACCGCAGGACAAAAGGACUCUGGCCACCCAGCAGGCCAUGGGCAUGCUGUCCACGGCCCCCAAGGUUGCUUCGAAGCCAAGGCAGGCAUCAAAAGCCAAAGUGGCCUUCUGCACCAGCAUCCCUCAGGACACCCUGCUGGGGAAGGCCCGGCCCGGCACAACAGCAGACUGAGGCCCCCACCCUGAAAAAGCCUAGGACAUUCCUGGGCACUGUCAUUUAGGGUGCUGUACAAAUCACCUCCGCCUAGAAAAUGGAAUUCAACAGUCAGGAUACAGAUUUCCAAGGCCAACUGUUGGCCCCAACAUGCAACAGUGAGACCAUAAGCCUCCCGUGGGCCACAUUUUGACAGUGGAUGCCCUUCAGGGUGAUAUAUGCUAUAAAGCAGUUUUCUAUCACCUAAGUGGUUUUUCUUGCCAACAAGAAUUUUUACCCAUCAGCACUACUGUGGCUGAAAAACUUCUCUUCAACAGUUCAGUGCGCCCUGUGCAGGAGUCAGCCCGGCAUCUGCUUGUACACACAGCUCCUUGCAUAGGUGUGGAGUUAGAUCUGGACAGUGAACUUCAGGAAGUCCUUUCUUAUAGGAGGCUAAUAGGGAUUGAGAAUAACAUGAGAAGAAAACGCUAAUAAAGGGAAACCUGAACACGCUGCUGUCAGCAUGUGUUUUCAAAGUGCAGCCUGCCUCAGAGUUCUUCGGAGCCUGAAAAGGGGUUUGAGAAAGAGCCCAGUAGGAGGGGCAGGAGGCCGACACACCUGACUUGGCCUGGGGCCCAGGAGGCAGGUGUAAGGGAGUGAAAAGAAAGGCUAGCCGGAGGCUGCGGGGGGAAGACCGCAGACUCCCUGCUGCUUCGCAUCCCUCCUGUGGCCUCCACUGCAGGCAGGACAAACCUGGAUGCCACCUGGAGCUGCUUCCUGAGUUGGCACACUAUCGUGUACACAGCAGUCUUCAGCCCCCUGGAAGGAGGCCAUAGUCGUGUGAGGAUGGCAAAGUCGAACAGGAAGCUUUGAGUGCCUUCCUCCACGAUGUCAACGAGGAGAUCCAGUGCCAGAUCGAGGUGGAUGGAACACCCAGGGGUAGGGGUGCAGGUGUGGGCAGUGAUGUCCCUUCCCCUCCCUCCCCUGGUCCCACAGACUGUGGCCAUGAGGCUGCAGGCUGGUGCUAUGACAGCAGAUUGCAGCACAGGGCCCUCCCCUCCAGCCCCCAGUGGGACAUCAAAACCACCCUGGGGCCAUUUGUGCAGGGCACCACCUCCAGUAUUGAUGGGGAAAAUAAACUCAGUAGAGCCACGACAGGGUGGAGAGAAGCAGGGACCAUUGUCUUCCUCAGGAGCGUGACAGCUGACCCCACAGACCAUGCUUGCUGGUACACACUGGUCCCAGACCCAGGCCUGUCGGACAUCAGCAGUGUGCUAAAAACGUGUAAGAUGUCACUACUCACCGUGUGUCCUAUCUAGUUGACAUGGGUGGAGUCAGCUAAGGGGUGAAUGUUCAUAUGCUCCCAAUUCACGUUGAAGCCCUAAUCCCCAAAGGGAUGGUAUUGGGGGUGGGGUCUUGGAGAGGUGAUUAGGUUAUGAGGGUGGAGCCCUGAUGAAUGGGAUUAGUGCUUUAUAAGGAGAGACACCAGAGAGAUGAUCUCUCUCUCCACCAUGUGAGGACACAGUGAGAAGACAGCCGUCUGCAGGCCCGGAAGAGAGCCCUCACCAGGAAAUGAAACUGUUGGCACCUUGAGACUUCCCAGCUUCCAGAACUGUAAGAAAUAAAUGUUUGUUGUUUAAGCCUUUCAGGCUACGGCUUUCUGUUACAGCAGCCUGAACUGAGAGUCCAUGCCGAGUUUUUGAAAUAAAUGUGAAUUCUGAUGUUA